GUUUAUGAGAAACAGUGUGUUUCAGAGAGGCUGUACCAGAAUUAACUCUGCUCAGAGUUAGAUUUGCUGGUCUUAAAGUACUUUUCCUCUUUAAGAUAAAAGAAGUUCUUCUAAAUCAGGAAUGGAUUGAAAUCUAAUGAACCGAAACUUUGGGUACUUCGGCCUUCAAGGGGCUCCUUUAUUGAGAAUCAAUGUCUUCUCCUAGGUAAUUGAUCACCCUAGACCCAGGGACACCCAAUUCAUCGUAAUCAUCAUGAAUAAUCAAAAAGUGGUAGCUGUGCUACUGCAAGAGUGCAAGCAAGUGCUGGAUCAGCUCUUGUUGGAAGCGCCAGAUGUGUCGGAAGAGGACAAGAGCGAGGACCAGCGCUGCAGAGCUUUACUCCCCAGCGAGUUAAGGACCCUGAUCCAGGAGGCAAAGGAAAUGAAGUGGCCCUUCGUGCCUGAAAAGUGGCAGUACAAACAAGCCGUGGGCCCAGAGGACAAAACAAACCUGAAGGAUGUGAUUGGCGCCGGGUUGCAGCAGUUACUGGCGUCCCUGAGGGCCUCCAUCCUCGCUCGGGACUGUGCGGCUGCGGCGGCUAUUGUGUUCUUGGUGGACCGGUUCCUGUAUGGGCUCGACGUCUCUGGAAAACUUCUGCAGGUCGCCAAAGGUCUCCACAAGUUGCAGCCAGCCACGCCAAUUGCCCCGCAGGUGGUUAUUCGCCAAGCCCGAAUCUCCGUGAACUCAGGAAAACUUUUAAAAGCAGAGUAUAUUCUGAGCAGUCUAAUAAGCAACAAUGGAGCAACGGGUACCUGGCUGUACAGAAAUGAAAGUGACAAGGUCCUGGUGCAGUCGGUCUGUAUACAGAUCAGAGGGCAGAUUCUGCAAAAGCUGGGGAUGUGGUACGAAGCAGCAGAGUUAAUAUGGGCCUCCAUUGUAGGAUAUUUGGCACUUCCUCAGCCGGAUAAAAAGGGCCUCUCCACGUCGCUAGGUAUACUGGCAGACAUCUUUGUUUCCAUGAGCAAGAACGAUUAUGAAAAGUUUAAAAACAAUCCACAAAUUAAUUUGAGCCUGCUGAAGGAGUUUGACCACCAUUUGCUGUCCGCUGCAGAAGCCUGCAAGCUGGCAGCUGCCUUCAGUGCCUAUACGCCGCUCUUCGUGCUCACAGCUGUGAAUAUCCGUGGCACGUGUUUAUUGUCCUACAGUAGUUCAAAUGACUGUCCUCCAGAAUUGAAAAACUUACAUCUGUGUGAAGCCAAAGAGGCCUUUGAGAUUGGCCUCCUCACCAAGAGAGAUGAUGAGCCUGUUACUGGAAAACAGGAGCUUCACAGCUUUGUCAAAGCUGCUUUCGGUCUCACCACAGUGCACAGAAGGCUCCAUGGGGAGACAGGGACGGUCCAUGCAGCAAGUCAGCUCUGUAAGGAAGCAAUGGGGAAGCUGUACAAUUUCAGCACUUCCUCCAGAAGUCAGGACAGAGAAGCUCUGUCUCAAGAAGUUAUGUCUGUGAUUGCCCAGGUGAAGGAACAUUUACAAGUUCAAAGCUUCUCAAAUGUAGAUGACAGAUCUUAUGUUCCCGAGAGUUUCGAGUGCAGGUUGGAUAAACUUAUCUUGCAUGGGCAAGGGGAUUUCCAAAAAAUCCUUGACACCUAUUCACAGCACCAUACUUCGGUGUGUGAAGUAUUUGAAAGUGAUUGUGGAAACAACAAAAAUGAACAGAAAGAUGCAAAAACAGGAGUCUGCAUCACUGCUCUAAAAACAGAAAUAAAAAACAUAGAUACUGUGAGUACUACUCAAGAAAAGCCACAUUGUCAAAGAGACACAGGAAUAUCUUCCUCCCUAAUGGGUAAGAAUGUUCAGAGGGAACUCAGAAGGGGAGGAAGGAGAAACUGGACCCAUUCUGAUGCAUUUCGAGUCUCCUUGGAUCAAGAUGUGGAGACUGAGACUGAGCCAUCGGACUACAGCAAUGGUGAGGGAGCUGUUUUCAACAAGUCUCUGAGUGGCAGCCAGACUUCCAGUGCUUGGAGCAACUUAUCAGGGUUUAGUUCCUCUGCAAGCUGGGAGGAAGUGAAUUAUCACGUUGACGACAGGUCAGCCAGAAAAGAGCCUGGCAAAGAACAUCUGGUGGACACUCAGUGUUCCACUGCCUUGUCUGAGGAGCUAGAGAAUGACAGGGAAGGCAGAGCUAUGCAUUCAUUGCAUUCACAGCUUCAUGAUCUCUCUCUUCAGGAACCCAACAAUGACAAUUUGGAGCCUUCUCAAAAUCAGCCACAGCAACAGAUGCCCUUGACACCCUUCUCGCCUCAUAAUACCCCAGGCAUUUUCUUGGCCCCUGGUGCAGGGCUUCUAGAAGGAGCUCCAGAAGGUAUCCAGGAAGUCAGAAAUAUGGGACCCAGAAAUACUUCUGCUCACUCCAGACCCUCAUAUCGUUCUGCUUCUUGGUCUUCUGAUUCUGGUAGGCCCAAGAAUAUGGGCACACAUCCUUCAGUCCAAAAAGAAGAAGCCUUUGAAAUAAUUGUUGAGUUUCCAGAAACCAACUGCGAUGUCAAAGACAGGCAGGGGAAAGAGCAGGGAGAAGAAAUUAGUGAAAGAGGCGCAGGCCCUACAUUUAAAGCUAGUCCCUCCUGGGUUGACCCAGAAGGAGAAACAGCAGAAAGCACUGAAGAUGCACCCUUAGACUUUCACAGGGUCCUGCACAAUUCUCUGGGAAACAUUUCCAUGCUGCCAUGUAGCUCCUUCACCCCUAAUUGGCCUGUUCAAAAUCCUGACUCCAGAAAAAGUGGUGGCCCAGUCGCAGAGCAGGGCAUCGACCCUGAUGCCUCCACAGUGGAUGAGGAGGGGCAACUGCUCGACAGCAUGGAUGUUCCCUGCACAAAUGGGCACGGCUCUCAUAGACUGUGCAUUCUGAGACAGCCGCCUGGUCAGAGGGCGGAGACCCCCAAUUCCUCUGUAAGCGGUAACAUCCUCUUCCCUGUCCUCAGCGAGGACUGCACUACCACAGAGGAAGGAAAUCAGCCUGGAAACAUGCUAAACUGCAGCCAGAACUCCAGCUCAUCCUCAGUGUGGUGGCUGAAAUCACCUGCAUUUUCCAGUGGUUCUUCUGAGGGGGACAGCCCUUGGUCCUAUCUGAAUUCCAGUGGGAGUUCUUGGGUUUCAUUGCCGGGAAAGAUGAGGAAAGAGAUCCUUGAGGCUCGCACCUUGCAACCUGAUGACUUUGAAAAGCUGUUGGCAGGAGUGAGGCAUGAUUGGCUGUUUCAGAGACUAGAGAAUACGGGGGUUUUUAAGCCCAGUCAACUCCACCGAGCACAUAGUGCUCUUUUGUUAAAAUAUUCAAAAAAAUCUGAACUGUGGACGGCCCAGGAAACUAUUGUCUAUUUGGGGGACUACUUGACUGUGAAGAAAAAAGGCAGACAAAGAAAUGCUUUUUGGGUUCAUCAUCUUCAUCAAGAAGAAAUUCUGGGGAGGUAUGUUGGGAAAGACUAUAAGGAGCAGAAGGGGCUCUGGCACCACUUCACUGAUGUGGAGCGACAGAUGACCGCACAGCACUAUGUGACAGAAUUUAACAAGAGACUCUAUGAACAAAACAUUCCCACCCAGAUAUUCUACAUCCCAUCCACAAUACUACUGAUUUUAGAGGACAAGACAAUAAAGGGAUGUAUCAGUGUGGAGCCUUACAUACUGGGAGAAUUUGUAAAAUUGUCAAAUAACACGAAAGUGGUGAAAACAGAAUACAAAGCCACAGAAUAUGGCUUGGCCUAUGGCCAUUUUUCUUAUGAGUUUUCUAAUCAUAGAGAUGUUGUGGUCGAUUUACAAGGUUGGGUAACCGGUAAUGGAAAAGGACUCAUCUACCUCACAGAUCCCCAGAUUCACUCCGUUGAUCAGAAAGUUUUCACUACCAAUUUUGGAAAGAGAGGAAUUUUUUACUUCUUUAAUAACCAGCAUGUGGAAUGUAAUGAAAUCUGCCAUCGUCUUUCUUUGACUAGACCUUCAAUGGAGAAACCAUGCACAUAGAAUACGGCACAGUCUGGUCCUUUGGGGCUUGGGCAGGGCCGUGACACAGGUUCUGGCCAAUGAUUUGCAAGAGGAAUUGAUCAGUAUCACUUUAAGUCCUGCAUUUAAUUGGCAGCACAAGAUCCUGCAGAGCCUCUUUCCCUCUGCCACAGUUAUCAAGAAUGGGUCAGGAGACCGCUGCUUCUGGGCAUAAGUCCUGCAAGGAAAGCAACAUGGAAAACAGCCCCAACUCACCCAUGAGGGAUGAAAAGCACUCUUGAGAAAGGCAUGUGUUGUUUAAGCCAUUGAGAUUUUAGAGCUUUUUGUCACUAUCUGUCAAGACUGAUACUACUGGGGCUUUUCCUAUUGAUUUGGGAGUUCUUUACAUAUUAAAAAAAUGUGAGCCUUUGUGAUACGAAUUCAAUUUGUUUUCCUGUCUUUUGACAUUUGACUUUGCAUAAAAGUUUAUCUGUGCAUAAUUUUAUAUGUAGUUGAAUUCAUCAAUCUUUUAUUUUGUAUGGCUUUUUGGUUAUGUAUAAUACUUAGAUCCUCCUUAUACUCUGAGUUUCUUUCUUUUUAAUUCUCCUGUAUUUCCUUCUAGUAUAAUUAAAUCUGUAAAAAGUAAGAUGGAAGAGUGGUACAGUUUUCUUUAUCCAGUCUGUCCUUGAUGGGCAUUUAGGUAGACUGGAUAAAGAAAAUGUGGUACAUAUACACCAUGGAACACUAUGUGUAUUAAUCCACUCUCACACUGCUAUGAAGAGAUACCUGAGACUGGGUAAUUUAGAAAGAAAAGAGGUUUAAUUAACUCACAGUUCCACAUGGCUGGGGAGACCUCAGGAAACUUACAAUCAUGGCAGAAGGCACCUCUUCAUAGGGUAGCAGGAGAGAGAAUGAGUGCCAGCAGGGGAAAUGCCAGAUGCUUAUAAAGCCAUCAGAUCUUGUGAGAAUUCAUUCACUCUCACGAGAACAGCAUGGGAAAAACUGCCUCAAUUACCUCCUACCAGGUCCUUCCCAUGACACAUGGGAAUUAUGGGACUACAAUUCGAGAUGAGAUUUGGGUGGGGACACAAAGCCAAACCAUAUCACAAUGUAACCAUAAAAAAGAAUGAGAUCAUGUCCUUUGCAGGGACAUGGAUAGAGCUGGAGGCCAUUAUUUUUAGCAAACUAAUGCAAGAACAGAAAACUAAAUACCACUUGUUCUCACUUAUAGGUGAGAGCUAAGUGAUGAGAGUAGGUGGACACAUAGAGGGAACAACACACACCAGGGCUUAUCAGAGGGUGGACAGUGGGAGGAGGGAGAGGAUCAGGAAAAAUAACUAAUGGGUACUAGGCUGAAUACCUGGGUGAUGAAGUAAUUCGCACAACAAACCCCCAUGACACAAACCUGCACAUGUACCCCUGAACUUAAAAUAAAAGUAAAAAAAAAAAAUCA